ACUCUUCCUCCAUCAGCCUGGCUGGCAGCAGCCUUGGACUCCGCCCGUGGAGCCCUGGGCCUGUUGACCCACCAGCUUAGGAGCACCCACCAAGCUCUGGGUAAGGAAGCUCACCUUCUGGGGCUCUUCUGGGAAAAUAGAGGUCAACGUGGAGGUACCAGGCCACCAUGCUCAGUCUCAAGCUGCCCCAACUUCUUCAAGUCCACCAGGUCCCCCGGGUGUUCUGGGAAGAUGGCAUCAUGUCUGGCUACCGCCGCCCCACCAGCUCGGCUUUGGACUGUGUCCUCAGCUCCUUCCAGAUGACCAACGAGACGGUCAACAUCUGGACUCACUUCCUGCCCACCUGGUGAGGGGAGGCUCCGCCCCAGGCCGCGGCCUUGAGCUCAGAGGGGGUACCCAGGCGGGCAGGGACCGUCCAGGCCCACGGGCUGCAGCGGCAGUCGCGGGGGUCCGCGGCGGCCUGAGCACGCGCCCGCCGCAGGUACUUCCUGUGGCGGCUCCUGGCGCUGGCGGGCGGCCCCGGCUUCCGUGCGGAGCCGUACCACUGGCCGCUGCUGGUCUUCCUGCUGCCCGCCUGCCUCUACCCCUUCGCGUCGUGCUGCGCGCACACCUUCAGCUCCAUGUCGCCCCGCAUGCGCCACAUCUGCUACUUCCUCGACUACGGCGCGCUCAGCCUCUACAGUCUGGGCUGCGCCUUCCCCUAUGCCGCCUACUCCAUGCCGGCCUCCUGGCUGCACGGCCACCUGCACCAGUUCUUUGUGCCUGCCGCCGCACUCAACUCCUUCCUGUGCACCGGCCUCUCCUGCUACUCCCGUUUCCUGGAGCUGGAAAGCCCUGGGCUCAGUAAGGUCCUCCGCACAGGAGCCUUCGCCUAUCCAUUCCUGUUCGACAACCUCCCACUCUUUUAUCGGCUCGGGCUGUGCUGGGGCAGGGGCCACGGCUGUGGGCAGGAGGCCCUGAGCACCAGCCAUGGCUACCAUCUCUUCUGCGCGCUGCUCACUGGCUUCCUCUUCGCCUCCCACCUGCCUGAAAGGCUGGCACCAGGACGCUUUGAUUACAUCGGUGAGGGCACGCCUGGCCCGGCCCGGGAAGAGGCAGGGGCAGAUGCCUUCCCAGAGCACAGAAUGAACUGGGCCACAGCCACCAGUUAUUCCACAUCUGUGCAGUGCUGGGCACCCACUUCCAGCUGGAGGCAGUGCUGGCUGAUAUGGGAUCACGCAGAGCCUGGCUGGCCACACAGGAACCUGCCCUGGGCCUGGCAGGCACAGUGGCCACACUGGUCUUGGCUGCAGCUGGGAACCUACUCAUUAUUGCUGCUUUCACAGCCACCCUGCUUCGGGCCCCCAGUACAUGCCCUCUGCUGCAGGGUGGCCCACUGGAGGGGGGUACCCAGGCCAAACAACAGUGAGGCCCCAUCCCUGACCCUGUCCUGGAGGGGGCAGAGGCCAGGCCCCAGUGCUGACGAGGAGCCCAGAUUUGGGCCUAAUCAGGUGGGGACGCAUCUCAGCCUGGAACCAACAGGGGCUGAGGAGAGAGGGCACAGGAGAGAGGGCAGAGAAGAGGAGGGGUGUCUAGGGGGACUGGCAGAGUGUGAGAGGGACCGUGAGGGGGCUCUUGAUGGGAGUGGAAGAAGUGCUGAGGGUCUGAGAGGGGAGAUGCAUGCGUGUCCAGGCUGAAGAUGCCCCUAUAUUCUGUCAAAGGUUGGCGGGGGGAGGUGUUGGGGUCCUUUCAUCUGGCUCCGUUUCUGGUGCUUCUGGAAGUCUCUGCUCAGCACAGGGAAGAACUAACACGACUAACCUAGGCCUACCCUGAAUGCUUCUUGCUAACCAGGCCGAGAGGCCACACACUUGCCCCCCCAUCCCCACAAACCAGGUAAUGCCAGUUUGCCAGCAGCUAUUUGCCUAUAGAGAUGAGUCUGUCCUGGUCAUAACUGUGUGCUCAAGGUGUCCAGGCUUUUGGGGGUGGGCCUAUCUGGGUGCAUUAUGGAUGGUUUGGUGGAUUGAGGUGUGGGGAGGAGGGUCCUAGGCUAGAGGGGGUAUCCCUAGUUAGACUUUGGGAAGCCACCUUCAACGUUUUCUGGAACAAGGCAGGUACAAAUAAAAAAAUAAAACUUUGGAAAGCACUUUCUAGAACUGAAGAAGGUAAAACCUCCUCACCCCCAUCCUCCUGACACCUCCCUCCCACACUCCAUAAACUGGACAGACUCACAGGCCCACA